GCGCUCUGCUCCAUCCCUGACCGGGCCGAGGCUGCUGGAUGCCGCGUCUCCGCUUCUGCUGCCUGCCGGGCGGGCUCCGGUGGCCGCAGCAAAGUGGGGCACCAAGGCCCUGUGCUAAGCACUCAUAAUCCUCUGGGGGUGCUACCCCUACAAACAGCACCCCCACCAUGUUUAACCUAAUGAAGAAAGACAAGGACAAAGAUGGCGGGCGGAAGGAGAAGAAGGAGAAAAAGGAGAAAAAGGAGCGGAUGUCAGCGGCAGAGCUUCGGAGCCUGGAGGAGAUGAGCCUGCGACGUGGCUUCUUCAACCUGAACCGCUCCUCCAAGCGUGAAUCCAAGACGCGCCUGGAAAUCUCCAACCCCAUCCCCAUCAAGGUGGCCAGCGGCUCUGACCUGCACCUGACUGACAUUGACUCCGAUAGUAACCGGGGCAGCGUCAUCCUGGACUCGGGCCACCUAAGUACAGCCAGCUCCAGCGAUGACCUCAAGGGUGAGGAGGGUAGCUUCCGUGGCUCGGUGCUGCAGCGGGCAGCCAAGUUCGGCUCACUGGCCAAGCAGAACUCACAGAUGAUUGUCAAGCGCUUUUCCUUCUCCCAGCGUAGCCGGGAUGAGAGCGCCUCAGAAACCUCGACGCCCUCAGAGCACUCUGCCGCCCCCUCGCCACAGGUGGAGGUGAGGACUCUAGAGGGACAGCUGGUGCAGCAUCCUGGCCCAGGCAUCCCUCGACCAGGGCACCGAUCCCGAGCCCCUGAGCUAGUGACUAAAAAGUUCCCAGUCGACCUGCGCCUGCCCCCCGUGGUGCCCCUGCCCCCACCUACCCUCCGGGAGCUGGAGCUGCAACGACGGCCCACUGGAGACUUUGGCUUCUCCCUGCGGCGCACAACCAUGCUGGAUCGGGGCCCCGAGGGCCAGGCCUGUCGGCGUGUGGUCCACUUUGCUGAGCCUGGUGCAGGCACCAAGGACCUGGCCCUGGGGCUGGUGCCAGGAGAUCGACUGGUGGAGAUUAAUGGGCACAAUGUGGAGAGCAAGUCCAGGGAUGAGAUUGUGGAGAUGAUCCGGCAGUCAGGGGACAGCGUGCGGCUCAAGGUGCAGCCCAUUCCAGAGCUCAGCGAGCUCAGCAGGAGCUGGCUGCGGAGCGGCGAGGGACCUCGCAGGGAGCCAUCCGAUCUGGACUCUGAGGCCGCCUCUCAUGCCCACAGCCAGGCGAAAACAGAAGAACAGAUUGCAGCAGAAGAGGCCUGGAAUGAGACGGAGAAGGUGUGGCUGGUCCAUAGGGACGGCUUCUCACUGGCCAGUCAACUCAAAUCUGAGGAGCUCAACUUGCCUGAGGGGAAGGUGCGUGUGAAGCUGGACCACGAUGGGGCCAUCCUGGAUGUGGAUGAGGAUGACGUUGAGAAGGCUAAUGCUCCCUCCUGCGACCGUCUGGAGGAUCUGGCCUCACUGGUGUACCUCAAUGAGUCCAGCGUCCUGCACACCUUGCGCCAGCGCUAUGGCGCUAGCCUGCUGCACACGUAUGCUGGCCCCAGCCUGCUGGUUCUUGGCCCCCGUGGGGCCCCUGCUGUGUACUCUGAGAAGGUGAUGCACAUGUUCAAGGGUUGUCGGCGGGAGGACAUGGCACCCCACAUCUAUGCAGUGGCCCAGACCGCAUACAGGGCGAUGCUGAUGAGCCGUCAGGAUCAGUCAAUCAUCCUCCUGGGCAGUAGUGGCAGUGGCAAGACCACCAGCUGCCAGCAUCUGGUGCAGUACCUGGCCACCAUCGCGGGCAUCAGCGGGAACAAGGUGUUUUCUGUGGAGAAGUGGCAGGCUCUGUACACCCUCCUGGAAGCCUUUGGGAACAGCCCCACCAUCAUUAAUGGCAAUGCCACCCGCUUCUCCCAGAUCCUCUCCCUGGACUUUGACCAAGCUGGCCAGGUGGCCUCAGCCUCCAUUCAGACAAUGCUUCUGGAGAAGCUGCGUGUGGCUCGGCGCCCAGCCAGUGAAGCCACAUUCAACGUCUUCUACUACCUGCUGGCCUGUGGGGAUGGCACCCUCAGGACAGAGCUCCACCUCAACCACUUGGCAGAGAACAAUGUGUUUGGGAUUGUGCCACUGGCCAAGCCUGAGGAAAAGCAGAAGGCAGCUCAGCAGUUUAGUAAGCUGCAGGCGGCCAUGAAGGUGCUGGGCAUCUCCCCCGAUGAACAGAAGGCCUGCUGGUUCAUUCUGGCUGCCAUCUACCACCUGGGGGCUGCGGGAGCCACCAAAGAGGCCCCCGAGGAGCAAGCGGAAGCUGCUGAAGCUGGGCGCAAGCAGUUUGCCCGCCAUGAGUGGGCCCAGAAGGCUGCGUACCUACUGGGCUGCAGCCUGGAGGAGCUGUCCUCAGCCAUCUUCAAGCACCAGCACAAGGGUGGCACCCUGCAGCGCUCCACCUCCUUCCGCCAGGGCCCCGAGGAGAGUGGCCUGGGAGAUGGGACAGGCCCGAAACUGAGUGCACUGGAGUGCCUUGAGGGCAUGGCGGCCGGCCUCUACAGCGAGCUCUUCACCCUUCUCGUCUCCCUGGUGAAUAGGGCUCUCAAGUCCAGCCAGCACUCACUCUGCUCCAUGAUGAUUGUCGACACCCCGGGCUUCCAGAACCCUGAGCAGGGUGGGUCAGCCCGCGGAGCCUCCUUUGAGGAGCUGUGCCACAACUACACCCAAGACCGGCUGCAGAGGCUCUUCCACGAGCGCACCUUCGUGCAGGAGUUGGAAAGAUACAAGGAGGAGAACAUCGAGCUGGCGUUUGACGACUUGGAACCCCCGACGGAUGACUCUGUGGCUGCUGUGGACCAGGCCUCCCAUCAGUCCCUGGUCCGCUCGCUGGCCCGCACAGACGAGGCGAGGGGCCUGCUCUGGCUAUUGGAAGAGGAGGCUCUGGUGCCAGGGGCCAGUGAGGACACCCUCCUGGAGCGCCUUUUCUCCUAUUAUGGCCCCCAGGAAGGUGACAAAAAAGGCCAAAGCCCCCUUCUGCACAGCAGCAAACCACACCACUUUCUCCUGGGCCACAGCCAUGGCACCAACUGGGUAGAGUACAAUGUGACUGGCUGGCUGAACUACACCAAGCAGAACCCAGCCACCCAGAAUGCCCCCCGGCUCCUGCAGGACUCCCAGAAAAAAAUCAUCAGCAACCUGUUUCUGGGCCGCGCAGGCAGUGCCACGGUGCUCUCUGGCUCCAUCGCGGGCCUGGAGGGCGGCUCGCAGCUGGCACUGCGCCGGGCCACCAGCAUGCGGAAAACCUUUACCACAGGCAUGGCGGCUGUCAAAAAGAAGUCACUGUGCAUCCAGAUGAAGCUACAGGUGGACGCCCUCAUCGACACCAUCAAGAAGUCAAAGCUGCAUUUUGUGCACUGCUUCCUGCCUGUAGCUGAGGGCUGGGCUGGGGAGCCCCGUUCCGCCUCCUCCCGCCGAGUCAGCAGCAGCAGUGAGCUGGACCUGCCCUCGGGAGACCACUGCGAGGCUGGGCUCCUGCAGCUCGACGUGCCCCUGCUCCGCACCCAGCUCCGCGGCUCCCGCCUGCUCGAUGCCAUGCGCAUGUACCGCCAAGGUUACCCUGACCACAUGGUGUUUUCCGAGUUCCGCCGCCGCUUUGAUGUCCUGGCCCCGCACCUGACCAAGAAACACGGGCGUAACUACAUCGUGGUGGAUGAAAGGCGGGCAGUGGAGGAGCUGCUGGAGUGCUUGGAUCUGGAGAAGAGCAGCUGCUGCAUGGGCCUGAGCCGGGUGUUCUUCCGGGCGGGCACCUUGGCACGGCUGGAGGAGCAGCGGGAUGAACAAACCAGCAGGAACCUAACCCUGUUCCAAGCAGCCUGCAGGGGCUACCUGGCCCGCCAGCACUUCAAGAAGAGAAAGAUCCAGGACCUGGCCAUUCGCUGUGUACAGAAGAACAUCAAGAAGAACAAAGGGGUGAAGGACUGGCCCUGGUGGAAGCUUUUUACCACAGUGAGGCCCCUCAUCGAAGUACAGCUGUCAGAGGAGCAGAUCCGGAACAAAGACGAGGAGAUCCAGCAGCUGCGGAGCAAGCUCGAGAAGGCGGAGAAGGAGAGGAACGAGCUGCGGCUCAACAGUGACCGGCUGGAGAGCCGGAUCUCAGAGCUGACAUCGGAGCUGACAGAUGAGCGUAACACAGGAGAGUCCGCCUCCCAGCUGCUGGACGCGGAGACAGCAGAGAGGCUCCGGGCUGAGAAGGAGAUGAAGGAACUGCAGACCCAGUACGAUGCACUGAAGAAGCAGAUGGAGGUUAUGGAAAUGGAGGUGAUGGAGGCCCGUCUCAUCCGGGCAGCGGAGAUCAACGGGGAAGUGGAUGAUGAUGAUGCAGGUGGCGAGUGGCGGCUGAAGUAUGAGCGGGCUGUGCGGGAGGUGGACUUCACCAAGAAACGGCUCCAGCAGGAGUUUGAGGACAAGCUGGAGGUGGAGCAGCAGAACAAGAGGCAGCUGGAACGGCGGCUCGGGGACCUGCAGGCAGAUAGUGAGGAGAGUCAGCGGGCUCUGCAGCAGCUCAAGAAGAAGUGCCAGCGACUGACGGCUGAGCUGCAAGACACCAAGCUGCACCUGGAGGGCCAGCAGGUCCGCAACCACGAACUGGAGAAGAAGCAGAGGAGGUUUGACAGUGAGCUCUCGCAGGCGCAUGAGGAGGCCCAGCGGGAGAAGCUGCAGCGGGAGAAGCUGCAGCGGGAGAAGGACAUGCUCCUCGCUGAGGCUUUCAGCCUGAAGCAGCAACUAGAGGAAAAAGACAUGGACAUUGCAGGGUUCACCCAGAAGGUUGUGUCUCUAGAGGCAGAGCUCCAGGACAUUUCUUCCCAAGAGUCCAAGGAUGAGGCUUCUCUGGCCAAGGUCAAGAAACAGCUCCGGGACCUGGAGGCCAAAGUCAAGGAUCAGGAAGAAGAGCUGGAUGAGCAGGCAGGGACCAUCCAGAUGCUGGAACAGGCCAAGCUGCGUCUGGAGAUGGAGAUGGAGCGGAUGAGACAGACCCAUUCUAAGGAGAUGGAGAGUCGGGAUGAGGAGGUGGAGGAGGCCCGGCAGUCGUGUCAGAAGAAGUUAAAACAGAUGGAGGUGCAGCUAGAGGAAGAGUAUGAGGACAAGCAGAAGGUUCUGCGAGAGAAGCGGGAGCUGGAGGGCAAGCUCGCCACCCUCAGCGACCAGGUGAACCGGCGGGACUUUGAGUCAGAGAAGCGGCUGCGGAAGGACCUGAAGCGCACCAAGGCCCUGCUGGCAGAUGCCCAGCUCAUGCUGGACCACCUGAAGAACAGUGCUCCCAGCAAGCGAGAGAUUGCCCAGCUCAAGAACCAGCUGGAGGAGUCAGAGUUCACCUGUGCGGCAGCCGUGAAAGCACGGAAAGCAAUGGAGGUGGAGAUCGAAGACCUGCACCUGCAGAUUGAUGACAUCGCCAAAGCCAAGACAGCGCUGGAGGAGCAGCUGAGCCGCCUUCAGCGUGAGAAGAAUGAGAUCCAGAACCGGCUGGAGGAAGAUCAGGAAGACAUGAACGAAUUGAUGAAGAAGCACAAGGCUGCCGUGGCUCAGGCUUCCCGGGACCUGGCUCAGAUAAAUGAUCUCCAAGCUCAGCUAGAAGAAGCCAACAAAGAGAAGCAGGAGCUGCAGGAGAAGCUACAAGCCCUCCAGAGCCAGGUGGAGUUCCUGGAGCAGUCCAUGGUGGACAAGUCCCUGGUGAGCAGGCAGGAAGCUAAGAUACGGGAGCUGGAGACACGCCUGGAGUUUGAAAGGACGCAAGUGAAACGGCUGGAGAGCCUGGCUAGCCGUCUCAAGGAAAACAUGGAGAAGCUGACUGAGGAGCGGGAUCAGCGCAUUGCAGCCGAGAACCGGGAGAAGGAACAGAACAAGCGGCUACAGAGGCAGCUCCGGGACACCAAGGAGGAGAUGGGCGAGCUUGCCAGGAAGGAGGCCGAGGCGAGCCGCAAGAAGCACGAACUGGAGAUGGAUCUAGAAAGCCUGGAGGCUGCUAACCAGAGCCUGCAGGCUGACCUAAAGUUGGCAUUCAAGCGCAUCGGGGACCUGCAGGCUGCCAUUGAGGAUGAGAUGGAGAGUGAUGAGAAUGAGGACCUCAUCAACAGUGAGGGAGACUCUGAUGUGGACUCGGAGCUGGAGGACCGUGUUGACGGGGUCAAGUCCUGGUUGUCAAAAAACAAGGGACCUUCCAAGGCAGCUUCUGAUGAUGGCAGCUUAAAGAGUUCCAGCCCCACCAGCUACUGGAAGUCCCUUGCCCCUGAUCGGUCAGAUGAUGAGCACGACCCUCUCGACAACACCUCCAGACCGCGAUACUCCCACAGUUAUCUGAGUGACAGCGACACAGAGGCCAAGCUGACGGAGACUAACGCAUAGCCCAGGGGAGUGGUUGGCAGCCCUCUCACCCCAGGGCCUGUGGCUGCCUGGGCACCUCUCCCAGGAAGUGGUGGGGCACCGGUCUCCCCCACCCGACUGCUGAUCUGCAUGGGAAACACCCUGACCUUCUUCUGUCAGGGGCACUUUCCAGGCUAUGGGUGUCUGAUGUCUCCACGUGGAAGAGGUGGGGGAAAGAGGAGUUUCUGAAGAGAACUUUUUGCUCCUCUGUCUCAAAAUGCCAGACUCUUGGCUUCUACCCUGUGUCACCGUGGGCAGUGGCAGGUGGCCUGGCACUGCAUGGAGCCAGCACGUUGACCUCCCUCUCAGCUCCCUGCUCAGGGACGGUGGACAGGUUGCCUACUGGGACACUCUAGGUUGCUGGGUCCAUGGGGAGGAUUGGGGGAGGAGAAGCAGUGCCUUCCCUCUCGUGUGGGGUGGGGGCUCUCUCUUCUUGGUGCCUGCUGUCUUUCUACUUUUUAAUUUAAAUACCCAACCUCUCCAUCACAGCUGCAUCCCUGAGAGUGGGAGGGGGCUGUAGUGGUAGCUGGGGCUCCCAAGAACGACUCGGGAAUGUCAUCUCCAUCUUCACCCUUCAGAGAGCAGUCCUUUCUCUGUGCAGCUGGAGACGCUGGUGAGGAGAGCCGGGUCCAGGUUCUUAAGAAUGAGGUGCGGAGGGGCUCUCCGGUGCUGCUGGGCUGGGUUGAGCAAGCCUACGCAGACAAGUGUGUGUGUGGACCAUCCGCACCUCCAGCCCCCACCCCACCCUCUUUGUCUCAGCGUGUUAUGUGCAAUGACCUAUUUAAGGUAAACCCAUUCCAACUACAGCAGUUCAGGGCUGAUCCAAGCACUGCCUCCCUCCUGCUCUGUCCAGGUGGUCUGGACCAUAAACUCAACUUGAGAGGGAAGGCUUGGGGUUGAGGACUUGUGAUCAGAAAAACUGAAGAUGGAAGUUUUGGCCGGUGCUCAUUAGACAUGAGUCCUCACUCUGUGUCCUGAGCCCGUGUCAUUCUUCCAACCUCCCUGCCCCCACACACUUAUCCCAGACACAACACCAUGUGGUCUGGAGGUCCCAGCCCCCACCCUAAAAAGGUUAUCCCUGAGAACUCCACCAGACUUGGGAGCCCAAGUGCAGUGCCUGGUGCUGCUCCCAUCUGCCGCCCCCCUUCUCUCCUGCAAUUGGUUUGUACUCACUGGGCUGUGCUCUCCCCUGUUUACCCGAUGUAUGGAAAUAAAGGCCCUUUUCCUCCUGGCUGCGCCAGUUUUCCUGCCUGUUCCUUCAGGCUCAGGCAAAGUCUGGAUUGGUCCUGGGGGUGGUGGGCAGAGGCAGGAUUCUGAUGGGGACCGUGAGGGCAUCACCCUGGUCUCUGGCCUGCUCCCCAAAGUGUCAGACCAGUGCCACUUAAAGAGCCUAGGCAGCUCAUUUUGGGGCAGGCAGAGGUAGUGGAAUGAGGGGAUUGGCCAAGGAAGACACAAGCCCCACCUUUUAUGUGAAGAGCCUAGGGACUGUGAUUCAGGUUAGCAAGGGUGGCAGAGACUCCAAGCCUCAUCCUCCCUAGCCUCCACAAGGGAAUGUUGAGGUCCCUCUGAUUGUUAAAUCUCACCAAUUACAGAGAUUCUCUUCUCUUCUCUUCUCUUCCUCCUUCCGUCCCUCCCUCUCUCCCUCUCUCUCUCUCUUUCUUUCUUUCAUUCUCUUUCUUUUUGGAUUCAAGCCCUUCUCAUUAGAACAUUUUUUAAAAGCUUAAUUUUAGCCAUUUCAAAGGUGACUUUUUGAUCAAAACUUGGCAGAACUAGCUCGGGCCCACAGGGCAAUGUGAAUAGGUUGGGAGUGCUGUCUCUGCCCUGCUCGGUCCCUGUCUUCAUGCCCUACUCCAUGCUUUGUUCCUUCAUUGACAGCUAAGAGGCAGCUCAUGCAGAAAGGCAAGAAACAAAUGACACCCCUCCUCCUCUUCUACCUUCUACCUUCUCAUUCUGUAGUGUGGCCAGUUAUAAUCCCUGAAUGAAUAAAGUAGUUUGGACAGAUGGGUGGGAAAAAAUAGCAAACAGCCCAAGUGCCGAGGCUCUGAUAAUGUCAGCCAUCCAGAAAGAGUCCAAAAGGGAAGAAGGGAGAAAAGUCUCCCCCAAAAUGAAUGGGACAGAGUGUGAAGUGGAUCUGUCUCGAACAGAGACUGCCCCCUCCAUUGCCCCACGAUAGAACAGAGAAGAGGAUAGAAACAAUAGUAAAAGGGAAGUUACUUGUCUUUUGGAGACAGAGUCUUGCUAUGUCGCCCAAGCUGGAAUGCAGUGGCAUGAUCUCAACUCACUGCAACCUCUACCUCCCGAGGUUCAAGCGAUUCUCCUGCCUAAACCCUCCGAGUAGCUGGGACUUAACAGACGUGUACCACCACGCCUGGCUAAUUUUUGUAUUUUUAAUAGAGACGGGGUUUCGCCAUGUUGAGCAGGCUGGUCUCGAACUUCUGACCUCAAGUGAUCUGCCUGCCUCGCCUCCCAAAGUGCUAGGAUUAUAGGCAUGAGCCACUGUGCCUGGCCUAAGUUACUUUUUUUUACAAAAAAAAAAAAAAAAAAAAAAAGGCUGCUAGCUUAUGUUCAGUUCUGUCACUCUCAUCUUUUAUUCCUGUUUUCACAUAGCGUGGUACAUUUUCUGUUUCUACUAGGGACUAGUGUGACAAACUCCCUGCCACCUUUAGAUGAAUUCCCAAAUCUGUUCACUCAUACUGAGUCAAGCCUCUGGUUAACUGGAAACUCCAACAUCAACCUCCAAUAACCCGGCCUGGGGUAAAAAGCUUUGUUCAAGUCAGAAAACAUAUUCAUUUGCUUAACAGUUGAGAAAUAUUUCAUGACUGCCUGCUGUGCCUAGGCCCCAUUCUGGGUGCUGGUGAUGGAUAAGGUCCCUUCCUUCAUAAAGUGGAGGAAGGUAGACACAAAAUACAUGCUGCACCUGCUAGUAUGCAUAAGCUUAGAGUGGGUAGAGAGGAACACAUCAUAGUAUCCAUCCUCCAGGGUUUUGCGGACGAGGGCUGGAGCAGACCCAUGUGGAAAUAAUUACAUAAGACCUAACAAGGAUGAAGAGGUUGCUUUGGACAUACUAUGGAGGGAGAUGCUCUCUUUGGCGGGGAGGAUUGGGAAAGCCUCUAAAAGGAGCUGCUAUUUUGACCAGGGCUUGAAAAUAGCACUUCCACAGGUACAGUUGCUGGGAAAGGCAUAUUGAGAAGAAGAAGAGUUUAAGUAAAGGUCCUGGGGCAGGGAAAGAGAGGUGCUGGUAGAACAUGCCACAGGCUGGCUGUGCAUUGUCACAUGACCAGUGCUUCUCCAAGUUUCAGUUGAGAAGGAGACAAUUCCCUUGGCCCCAGAGGAGUCCAGGAGCCUUUAGGGCCACCAAAGCCCAUCUUUAUUUUGGGUGUACCUUGAAGGCUCUGCUGUUGACCUUACCUGUACACUCAUGGUACCUCUGGUCCCUAAGAUGUUGCAGAAGGCAAAUCUGGCCCUUUGCCAGGCUCAAAGCCAGCCUGCUAGAUCCUCCUCUAUAACUGCAGAUCCCCGGGAUUGCUCUGACUCCUGAAUAAGCAUGGGCGGGAACCAGUGCCCCUGUGGGACUCCCCAUGGUGCCCAGUCUGUGCCCAGAAAAUAAAGUGGCAGGCAGUGACCCCUAAA